AGUGGCUGAAGGCAGAACAAGAACACAGGGGUCCACUUUCUAAGGCCUCGUGGCCUUUAUAGCUCUACAAACCCCAAGUGUCCCUAACUCUUCUCUCUCAAGGGAUACAGACUCUGAUAUAACUGGAUUCUAUGCUCCAAACUCAAAGGGAAUGCAGUAGAAGCUGAAAAACGAAUUUUUUGAUGUAUUUUUCUAGAACACUAUUGUCUAAUUUUCAUGGCAGCCUAGCAUGGUGCAAGGUUGUCUUGGUUUAAGUUCCAGGAAAAAAUACCCAGCAAGAAGAAUCUGAGUACAAGAAAUUUUGGGGAGAGAUGGUCCCAGGAAGCAAAGGAGGGGAAGAGAGGAAGCAAGACAAGGAAGGGGAAAAAUAAGCCUCAGAGUCAUCCCAACCAAGAGGCAAGGGAGAUGGGGAAUCUUCCGAUAAUUCUGCCGCCGCGACUUUAACCGUGCGCAAGGCGAGAGCUCGAAACAAACAUCACAUCUAAAUUAAAAAAAAAAAAAAGCGGAAGAAGCGGCCGAGGCGGCGGCGGGAGGAGAGGAGGAGGGGCCGCGCGCGGCGGCCCGAGGCGGCGGCGGGGACGCGGGGACGCGAGGACGCGGCUUUGUGCAGGCGGGUCGCGGGGCGCCCAUGGCGGAGUGCGGCCGGGGGGGCGCCGCCGGCGGGGCCCUGCCCACCUCCCCGGGCCCGGCCCUCGGCGCCAAGGGCGCCCUGAAAGCCGGAGUGGGGGAAGGCGGUGGCGGGGGAGGUCGCCUCGGCCACGGGCGGGCGCGCUAUGACAGCGGCGGGGUUUCCAACGGAGACUGCAGCCUCGGCGUGUCCGGGGACGAAGCCCGGGCUAGCCCUACCAGGGGACCCCGCGGCGUUGCGCUCGCCCCGACCCCCAGCGCGGUCGUCUGUACCCUCCCCCGGGAGAGCAAGCCGGGCGGCCUGCCCCGCCGGAGCAGCAUCAUCAAGGAUGGUACAAAACAGAAGAGGGAACGGAAAAAGACAGUCUCAUUCAGCAGCAUGCCAACAGAGAAGAAGAUCAGCAGUGCAAGUGAUUGUAUUAAUUCAAUGGUUGAGGGUUCAGAACUCAAAAAGGUUCGCUCCAACUCUAGAAUUUAUCAUAGGUACUUUUUACUGGAUGCUGACAUGCAGAGCCUAAGGUGGGAGCCAUCUAAGAAGGAUUCUGAGAAAGCCAAGAUUGACAUUAAAUCCAUCAAGGAAGUGAGAACAGGAAAAAACACAGACAUAUUCCGCAGCAAUGGCAUUUCUGACCAGAUAUCUGAAGAUUGUGCGUUUUCCGUCAUAUAUGGAGAGAAUUAUGAGUCACUGGAUUUGGUUGCCAACUCCGCAGAUGUUGCAAACAUCUGGGUUACAGGACUGCGGUACCUAAUUUCUUAUGGAAAACAUACACUUGAUAUGUUAGAAAGUAGCCAAGAUAACAUGAGGACUUCUUGGGUUUCACAAAUGUUUAGUGAAAUUGAUGUAGAUAACCUUGGACAUAUAACUCUGUGUAAUGCUGUGCAAUGUAUCAGAAACCUCAAUCCUGGUUUAAAAACGAGCAAAAUUGAGCUUAAGUUCAAAGAAUUGCAUAAAUCAAAGGACAAAGCUGGUACCGAGGUCACAAAGGAAGAAUUUAUUGAGGUUUUUCAUGAGCUUUGUACUAGACCUGAAAUUUAUUUCCUUUUAGUUCAGUUUUCAAGCAAUAAAGAAUUCCUUGAUACCAAGGACCUUAUGAUGUUUCUUGAGGCAGAACAGGGUGUGGCACAUAUAAAUGAGGAAAUAAGCCUUGAAAUUAUUCACAAAUAUGAACCAUCCAAAGAGGGUCAGGAAAAGGGCUGGCUCUCCAUAGACGGGUUCACUAAUUACCUUAUGUCACCUGACUGUUAUAUAUUCGAUCCAGAACAUAAGAAGGUCUGUCAGGAUAUGAAGCAACCUCUGUCUCAUUACUUUAUAAACUCAUCUCAUAAUACAUACUUAAUAGAGGAUCAGUUCCGAGGUCCCUCCGACAUCACAGGAUAUAUUCGAGCUCUUAAAAUGGGUUGCCGGAGUGUUGAAUUAGAUGUAUGGGAUGGGCCGGACAAUGAACCUGUAAUUUACACAGGCCACACCAUGACCUCUCAGAUAGUUUUCCGCAGUGUCAUUGAUAUUAUUAACAAGUAUGCAUUCUUUGCUUCAGAGUAUCCUCUUAUCUUGUGUUUAGAAAACCACUGUUCCAUUAAACAACAGAAGGUAAUGGUUCAGCACAUGAAGAAACUUUUAGGAGACAAGCUCUAUACAACAUCACCCAAUGUUGAGGAAUCUUAUCUACCAUCCCCAGAUGUCCUGAAAGGGAAAAUACUAAUUAAAGCAAAGAAGCUGUCCUCAAAUUGCUCUGGGGUAGAAGGAGAUGUUACUGACGAAGAUGAAGGAGCAGAAAUGUCUCAGAGGAUGGGAAAAGAGAACAUGGAGCAACCCAAUAAUGUGCCUGUGAAGCGAUUUCAGCUUUGUAAAGAACUGUCUGAACUGGUCAGCAUCUGCAAAUCAGUUCAGUUCAAAGAAUUUCAGGUGUCGUUUCAGGUUCAGAAGUACUGGGAAGUCUGUUCCUUUAAUGAAGUGCUUGCCAGCAAGUACGCCAAUGAAAAUCCAGGGGACUUUGUAAAUUACAACAAACGUUUUCUUGCUAGGGUUUUUCCCAGUCCAAUGAGAAUUGAUUCCAGUAACAUGAAUCCUCAAGAUUUUUGGAAAUGUGGUUGCCAAAUUGUAGCCAUGAACUUUCAGACACCAGGACUGAUGAUGGACCUGAAUAUUGGCUGGUUUAGGCAGAACGGAAACUGUGGCUAUGUCCUCCGGCCAGCCAUCAUGAGGGAGGAGGUCUCCUUCUUCAGCGCCAAUACAAAAGACUCUGUCCCAGGGGUCUCACCUCAACUUCUUCACAUUAAAAUCAUCAGUGGGCAGAACUUUCCCAAGCCCAAAGGAUCAGGUGCCAAAGGUGAUGUGGUAGAUCCUUAUGUCUAUGUUGAAAUCCAUGGAAUCCCUGCUGAUUGUGCAGAACAAAGGACAAAAACAGUGCACCAGAAUGGAGACGCUCCCAUUUUUGAUGAAAGCUUUGAAUUUCAAAUCAACCUGCCUGAACUGGCCAUGGUGCGCUUUGUAGUGCUGGAUGAUGACUACAUUGGGGAUGAAUUCAUCGGCCAGUACACAAUUCCCUUUGAAUGUUUACAGACGGGCUACCGCCAUGUCCCCCUGCAGUCCUUAACUGGAGAGGUCCUUGCACAUGCUUCUUUAUUUGUCCACGUGGCUAUUACUAACCGAAGAGGAGGAGGAAAGCCUCAUAAAAGGGGCCUUUCUGUGAGAAAAGGGAAGAAAUCCAGGGAAUAUGCAUCUUUGAGAACACUGUGGAUUAAAACCGUGGAUGAGGUAUUCAAGAAUGCCCAGCCCCCUAUACGGGAUGCCACAGAUCUGAGAGAAAACAUGCAGAAUGCGGUGGUGUCAUUCAAGGAGCUGUGUGGCCUCUCCUCUGUGGCCAAUCUCAUGCAGUGCAUGUUGGCGGUGUCUCCCCGCUUUCUGGGGCCCGAUAACACACCCCUAGUGGUCCUAAAUCUCAGCGAGCAGUACCCCACAAUGGAGCUGCAGGGAAUUGUGCCGGAGGUUCUGAAGAAGAUCGUAACAACUUAUGACAUGAUGAUUCAGUCCCUCAAGGCGUUGAUUGAAAAUGCAGAUGCUGUAUAUGAAAAGAUCGUACAUUGUCAGAAGGCAGCCAUGGAAUUCCAUGAACACUUGCACAGCAUAGGCACCAAGGAAGGUUUGAAGGAAAGAAAACUACAAAAAGCAGUGGAGAGCUUUACCUGGAAUAUUACCAUCUUAAAGGGACAAGCAGAUCUUUUGAAAUAUGCUAAGAAUGAGACAUUGGAGAACCUGAAACAAAUCCAUUUUGCUGCUGUUUCAUGUGGACUGAAUAAACCAGGCACCGAAAAUGCUGAUGUCCAGAAGCCACGCCGGAGCUUGGAAGUCAUACCCGAAAAAGCAAACGAUGAAACUGGAGAAUGAGGAAACUUACAAUAAACCAUUAUGGAGUUUAUAACUCUAGGACCAAUUGUAGUCAGAUGGGACAUUUGCUUUGCACUCACUAAUGAGAAUAAUAUUCGGGAUUUUAAAGCACAACUGGAAUAGCUAAUUACAGUCUAUUAAAACUGUGAAUGUAUGUAGCAAUCCUGCGUGUGAAGGCAAAUAAACUCUUUAACAGGCAAUUAUAUUGCUGGCCAAAAUAUGCUAUAUUUGUAUACAAAGACAUUCUAACUCAGUUCCAGUAUGAAGAAAGAUUAUUCACUCUAGCUCCACUGAGAAACAUUUUCCUAAGUGAAAACAAUUUCUUAAGAUGGAAAUGGAUUGGAUUGUCAAAUUAUUAUUUAUUGGAGAAAAAAACCUGAUCUACACAUUUUUACUUAUAUGGGGUUGCCAGAGUCUCUGGGUUCUAGAUGAUUUUGGUGGCAUGCUUGCUGAGCCAUAAUUACUAAAGAGAAUGUAAGUGGACGGGUUCCCUGAAUCCCCGGGGUCCUUGGAGAGCCAUCGAGGAGAAUGUGCAAUUGGACUGAAGCUCCCUGGCUGAAGAUACAUGCCGAGUCAGCACAUGGGUAGAGAUGAUGUAAAAGCAGCCAAUCUGGAAACAAUACAUUGUAAAUAGUUUUUCAUUGUAUGAAGUAGUGUUCACAUUAAAAAGAUGUUUUAUGAUAUUUCUCCAAUA